UGCAUUAAGAAGUCUUCAGCAGUGAUAUUAGACAUUGGGGCAUGCUCUUACAGGCAAUGGGUGGUGUCAUAAAGAGCAUAUUUACAUUCGUUUUAAUUGUGGAAUUUAUAAUUGGAAAUUUAGGAAAUAGUUUCAUAGCACUGGUGAACUGUAUUGACUGGGUCAAGGGAAGAAAGAUCUCUUCGGUUGAUCGGAUCCUCACUGCUUUGGCAAUCUCUCGAAUUAGCCUGGUUUGGUUAAUAUUCGGAAGCUGGUGUGUGUCUGUGUUUUUCCCAGCUUUAUUUGCCACUGAAAAAAUGUUCAGAAUGCUUACUAAUAUCUGGACAGUGAUCAAUCAUUUUAGUGUCUGGUUAGCUACAGGCCUCGGUACUUUUUAUUUUCUCAAGAUAGCCAAUUUUUCUAACUCUAUUUUUCUCUACCUAAAGUGGAGGGUUAAAAAGGUGGUUUUGGUGCUGCUUCUUGUGACUUCGGUCUUCUUGUUUUUAAAUAUUGCACUGAUAAACAUCCAUAUAAAUGCCAGUAUCAAUGGAUACAGAAGAAACAAGACUUGCAGUUCUGAUUCAAGUAACUUUACACGAUUUUCCAGUCUUAUUGUAUUAACCAGCACUGUGUUCAUUUUCAUACCCUUUACUUUGUCCCUGGCAAUGUUUCUUCUCCUCAUCUUCUCCAUGUGGAAACAUCGCAAGAAGAUGCAGCACACUGUCAAAAUAUCCGGAGACGCCAGCACCAAAGCCCACAGAGGAGUUAAAAGUGUGAUCACUUUCUUCCUACUCUAUGCCAUUUUCUCUCUGUCUUUUUUCAUAUCAGUUUGGACCUCUGAAAGGUUGGAGGAAAAUCUAAUUAUUCUUUCCCAGGUGAUGGGAAUGGCUUAUCCUUCAUGUCACUCAUGUGUUCUGAUUCUUGGAAACAAGAAGCUGAGACAGGCCUCUCUGUCAGUGCUACUGUGGCUGAGGUACAUGUUCAAAGAUGGGGAGCCCUCAGGUCACAAAGAAUUUAGAGAAUCAUCUUGAAUAUAUUAGAAAAAAAAUAGCUCCUAAGAAAUUCUUGUAUGUUAUAUAAAUUUAUACUUCCUUAAGAUUCUUUCAUUGUGUAUAACUUUGUGAAUUUUACAAAGAUAUGCUUGGAAUCAACACCAUCCAAACAUAUCACAAAUUAGGAUAUAUGAAAGUAUGUAUAUUACCAUACAGAGAAGAAUGCGAAUACUAUAAAGAGUUCUUAUACAAACAGAUAAUAUAGAUUUUGUAUCAAUCAUUCACCUUUUUUGAGAUUUUUAAAUGAGAAAACCUAUAAUGUAUAAAAUACAUGUGUGUAUGUAUGUAUGUGACACAGUUACUAAAAAUAGGCUUCUUAAACUUACAUCUCAAUCUGGUAGAUAAAGUACAUAAAAGAAUAUGGAAUUUUAGUACCUAUAUUAAGUGUUUUUAAUUUUUGUAUAAUAUUUAGUACCUGAUUAGCGUGUAUGCAAAAAAGUAAUUUGCUUCGUUUGUUGAAUUAGAAGCCAGCUGCCUUACUAAACUACCACAUUUGCUUUGCUCAUUCUCUUGGCUUUGCAGAUAGAAAAUUAUAUCAUCUGCAUAUAGUGACUUAUAAUGAUUAUUUUACUUCUCCAUUUUACUACUUGUAAUUCUUUUUUGGUAUCAGUUGUAUAAUGAAAUGGUUUGAACAUUCAAAGUGUUAAGUAAUCCUGAUCGUAACUGCUGUCUUUGCAAAUGGAGUGUUUUCUAGUGUUUUAACAAUAAACGUAAUACUGACUCUAGCUUUGAGAUAAAUUCUUUUAAAAAUAUUCUUCAGGGAGAAUAUUUGUUUCCUAUCUUCCUGUGUAUAGUAUUGUAAUAAAAUCUCUGUUAAAAACUA